AUAAAUUGUGCAAGGGUGCUAUAGACGCACAAACGACCGCGAGCCACAAAUCAAGCACACAUAUCAAAAAACAAAUGAGCUCUUAUUUUGUAAACUCAUUUUGCGGUCGCUAUCCAAAUGGCCCGGACUACCAGUUGCAUAAUUAUGGAGAUCAUAGUUCCGUGAGCGAGCAAUUCAGGGACUCGGCGAGCAUGCACUCCGGCAGGUACGGCUACGGCUACAAUGGCAUGGAUCUCAGCGUCGGCCGCUCGGGCUCCGGCCACUUUGGCUCCGGAGAGCGCGCCCGCAGCUACGCUGCCAGCGCCAGCGCGGCGCCCGCCGAGCCCAGGUACAGCCAGCCGGCCACGUCCACGCACUCUCCUCAGCCCGAUCCGCUGCCCUGCUCCGCCGUGGCCCCCUCGCCCGGCAGCGACAGCCACCACGGCGGGAAAAACUCCCUAAGCAACUCCAGCGGCGCCUCGGCCGACGCCGGCAGCACCCACAUCAGCAGCAGAGAGGGGGUUGGCACGGCGUCCGGAGCCGAGGAGGACGCCCCUGCCAGCAGCGAGCAGGCGAGUGCGCAGAGCGAGCCGAGCCCGGCGCCGCCCGCCCAACCCCAGAUCUACCCCUGGAUGCGCAAGCUGCACAUAAGUCAUGACAACAUAGGCGGCCCGGAAGGCAAAAGGGCCCGGACGGCCUACACGCGCUACCAGACCCUGGAGCUGGAGAAGGAGUUCCACUUCAACCGUUACCUGACCCGCAGAAGGAGGAUUGAAAUAGCACAUGCUCUUUGCCUCUCCGAGAGACAAAUUAAAAUCUGGUUCCAAAACCGGAGAAUGAAGUGGAAAAAAGAUAAUAAGCUGAAAAGCAUGAGCAUGGCCGCGGCAGGAGGGGCCUUCCGUCCCUGAGUAUCUGAGCGUUUAAAGUACUGAGCAGUAUUAGCGGAUCCCGCGUAGUGUCAGUACUAAGGUGACUUUCUGAAACUCCCUUGUGUUCCUUCUGUGAAGAAGCCCUGUUCUCGUUGCCCUAAUUCAUCUUUUAAUCAUGAGCCUGUUUAUUGCCAUUAUAGCGCCUGUAUAAGUAGAUCUGCUUUCUGUUCAUCUCUUUGUCCUGAAUGGCUUUGUCUUGAAAAAAAAUAGAUGUUUUAACUUAUUUAUAUGAAGCAAGCUGUGUUACUUGAAGUAACUAUAACAAAAAAAGAAAAGAGAAAAAAAAACACACAAAAAGUCCCCCUUCAAUCUCGUUUAGUGCCAAUGUUGUGUGUUGCACUCAAGUUGUUUAACUGUGCAUGUGCGUGGAAGUGUUCCUGUCUCAAUAGCUCCAAGCUGUUAAAGAUAUUUUUAUUCAAACUACCUAUAUUCCUUGUGUAAUUAAUGCUGUUGUAGAGGUGACUUGAUGAGACACAACUUGUUCGACGUGUAGUGACUAGUGACUCUGUGAUGAAAACUGUGACUCCAAGCGGUGUGUCCCUGCGUGCCUUUAUAGGACCCUUUGCACGAACUCUGGAAGUGGCUCUUAUAAGCGCAGCUUCAGUGAUGUAUGUUUUUGUGAACAAAGUUACAAAUAUUGUCCAAGUCUGGCUGUUUUAAGCAAACUGUGAUCAGCUUUUUUUUUUUUUUUUUUUUUUUUGUAUUUGUUUUUAAGGAAAAAAUACUGACUGGAACAAAAAAUAAACUUUCUAUUGUAAGUUC